ACUGACACGCAGCUUUGGUUAAAGAGCGGGCGCACAGGAGGGGAGGAGACCGCGCGCGGGACGGGGAGGAAUGGCCUGUCCGCGUUAAACCAUCACAAGCCAUGGUUGCGGAAGGGCCACGCGUCCCCCAGUAGGAGAAUGACUCCGAUUCGUGACCCUCAGCGCCGGUGCAUGUCGAUGUAAGUGCGAGGCCGGCGAGCAGAGUGUGAGUGGGGGUUGGUGGUGAGGGGAGAUUCUGAUGCAAUCGGCCCGGAAAGGAGGAGAGCCAGGCGAGCGCGGACUGGGGCGGCCACGCCACUCCGCCAGAAGGUCGCCAGGAGCCUCCGCCCUUCACCUUCCUCCGAAAUCCGCCAGGCCACGCCAAGCUCCCUGCCCAACCCUUACUGACGGGGGCCACAUUUUCCCGGCCUCCGCAGCCAGACCUUGACACAAAGGACAUCAAACUGCCGAGGGUAAAAACCCCGGAAGGGCGGACACCUCCACAUCGCCUUUUGCCACCUUUCCCUUUAUUUCCGGAGAGUCAAGGAAACUUUUGAGCUAUUUACAGCUUGUAGCAAUUAUGUAAAGUAUACUCCUCUGAACAAAAUUUGGAGCAUGUUUGUUUCUCUCUACCUGAUUUCCCCAGAAUCUGGAAACUAUCUGUGAGUAUUCUCAACUUUUAGCAAUAUAGUUAUUUGCAUAAGUGCAAUAAGAAUCUGUUUUCUUUUGUAACAGGACACAAUUGGAGAAACUGGUUAUUUUACCAAGGCUUUGACUGGAACAGCAUGCUUUCCUUUAAGGAAUCAAACCUGACUUGUAAAGCCAAGCAAAUCCCUUUGGGGAAUUGGCCUCAUACUUGCCUACACAGACCUCAAAAGGAGAGAAAUUUACCCAACUCAUAGGUAUUUGAGGGUUCAAACUCAUUGCAAGGCUUGGUUCUAAAAAGUCUUAUCUGAGAUUCCUUCUAUGGAGCAGAGUUCCAUCAAAGCGAAAUUACAAAAGGCUUAUGUGAAAAAUAAUUAUUCUUGCUGCACUUUAUACAAAAAAUCAGGCCAAGUAUAAUAAAGCAAAUCAGUGUUACUAUGAUUUGUCUUUAGUAAAAAAUGGGAAACUGGAGAGAGAAACUGUGUUUCAAGAAUUAUGCUACACUUGUUAUUAAAUUCUAGUCUCAUCAGUUGCUUUUAAGUUAGUUGCUGCAAUUUAUUCCUGUGAACCAACCAGUGAUCUCUAGCUGCUGCUCAGAAGAAACAAGAGGGAUGAGUAAUGUAAAAAUCUGGAUCAAUAUUCCAAUUCUGGACAUAUUGGAAUCAUCUAGCAAUGUCAUAUCAGCUUGGUUCCAACAGUUGCCCUUAUAAUUUGGAACUUCUUAUAAUUUAGUUUACUUGAGAUAAUUUUUACUUAUUUUGCUUUACUCUUGUGGAAUACAUUGCUAUGGCACUCUGUAUAGGCAUAAGGAUAAGCUUACUCAAUGUUUUCUUAAAUUGAACACUUAUUCAUCUUCCAAAUAUUACUUUUUGUCAGAACUUAAGAGUCAUAAAUGUCCCUCACCAUACUGAUGCUUUCUGACUGAGCGCGUCUCUACCCUGAACACAAGAUAUUCUCAUAGUUAGGUAGGAAUACCAUCACCCCUAUUCAGCCUGAAGAAGUUACUAAAGAUGGAUUUUCAUCCCUGUGCAGCCCUUAGGAUUAAGGGUUCUCUUAUAAAAGGGAGGGGGGAAAUGUCAGAGGCAUGUGAACCAGAGCAACUCCAUUUUAAAUAGGAGCUGAGUAAAAUGAGGCUGAGAGCCACUGAGCUGCAUUUCCAGAUGGUUAAAGCAUUCUAAGUCACAGAAUGAGAUAGGAGGUUAGCACAAAGUACAGGUCAUAAAGACCUUAAUGAUAAAACAGGUUGCAGUAAAGAAGCUGGCUAAAACCCACCAAAACCAAGAUGGUGAUGAGAGUGACCUCUGGUCGUCCUCACUGCUACACUCUCACCAGUGCCAUGACAGUUUACAAAUGCCAUGGCAACAUCUGGAAGUUGCCCUAUAUGGUCUAAAAAGGGGAGGCAUGAAUAAUCCACUUUGUUUAGCAUAUCAUCAACAAAUAACCAUAAAAAUGGGCAACCAGCAGCCCUUGGGGCCGCUCUGUCUGUGGAGUAGCCAUUCUUUUAUUCCUUUACUUUCUUAAUAAUCUUGCUUCUGCUUUGCACCUUGGGCUUGCCCUGAAUUCUUUCUUUCCUGAGAUCCAAGAACCCUCUUUUGGGGUCCAGAUCAGGACCCCUUUCUUGUAACACUUCUGGUCCCAAACAUUUUUGAUAAGAAAUACUCAAACUGUAUUAACUACAGUCCUCAUGUUGUACAUUUGCUCCCUAGACUUAUUCAUCCUACACAUCUGCAACUUCAUAUCCUUUGACCUACAUCUCCACAUUUCCUCCCCAAACUCUUUAUAACAACUGUUUUAUUCUCUAUGUCUGUGUAUCAGACUUUUUUUUUUUUUUUUUCAAAAAAAGAUACCAUGUAUACAUGAGAUCAUGCAGUAUUUUUCUUUCUGUUUCUGGAUUGUUUUACUUACCAUUAUGUCCUCCAGAUUCAUCCAGGUUGUGGCAAAUGAGAGGAUCCCCUUCUUUUUUAAGGUUGAAUAACAUUUUAUUUUAUAUGUGCCUGUGUUUCUUAUCCAUUCACAUCCAUGGGCACUUAGAUUGUUUCCAUAUCUUGGCUAUUGUGAAUAAUGCUGCAACGAACAUAGAAAGAACAUUUCUAUGUGCAUAGAAAAACCAUGGAAGGCCAUACAACAAUUAUAUAUAUAUAUGAGUGAUCAUCUCUGCUUGCUGAGAUAACAGAUAUUUAUUGAGUGUCUACUGUGUGCCAGGCACUAUAUCUAUGUGCAUAGAAAAACCCUGGAAGGCCAUACAACAAUAUAUAUAGAGUGAUCGUCUCUGCUUGCUGAGCUAACAGGGGUGUCAAGCUUCCAUUUUGGUAUCUACUUCUAAAUACACUCAGAACAGGAGAAAUUUGGACUAAUUUUCAAACUACAGACACUUUCUAAUCAUGAUGCAUUUCAAAAGUGGACUCGAAUUAACUGAGUUGCAAAACAUGACAGUGCCCGAGGAUGAUAACAUUAGCAAUGACUCCAAUGAUUUCACCGAAGUAGAAAAUGGUCAGAUAAAUAGCAAGUUUAUUUCUGAUCGUGAAAGUAGAAGAAGUCUCACAAACAGCCAUUUGGAAAAAAAGAAGUGUGAUGAGUAUAUUCCAGGUACAACCUCCUUAGGCAUGUCUGUUUUUAACCUAAGCAACGCCAUUAUGGGCAGUGGGAUUUUGGGACUCGCCUUUGCCCUGGCAAACACUGGAAUCCUACUUUUUCUGGUACUUUUGACUUCAGUGACAUUGCUGUCUAUAUAUUCAAUAAACCUCCUAUUGAUCUGUUCAAAAGAAACAGGCUGCAUGGUGUAUGAAAAGCUGGGGGAACAAGUCUUUGGCACCACAGGGAAGUUCGUAAUCUUUGGAGCCACCUCUCUACAGAACACUGGAGCAAUGCUGAGCUACCUCUUCAUCGUAAAAAAUGAACUACCCUCUGCCAUAAAGUUUCUAAUGGGAAAGGAAGAGACAUUUUCAGCCUGGUACGUGGAUGGCCGCGUUCUGGUGGUGAUAGUUACCUUUGGCAUAAUUCUCCCUCUGUGUCUCUUGAAGAACUUAGGGUAUCUUGGCUAUACUAGUGGAUUUUCCUUGAGCUGUAUGGUUUUUUUCCUAAUUGUGGUUAUUUACAAGAAAUUUCAAAUUCCCUGCAUUGUUCCAGAGCUAAAUUCAACAAUAAGUGCUAAUUCAACAAAUGCUGACACGUGUACGCCAAAAUAUGUUACCUUCAAUUCAAAGACCGUGUAUGCUUUACCCACCAUUGCAUUUGCAUUUGUUUGCCACCCGUCAGUCCUGCCAAUUUACAGUGAGCUUAAAGACCGAUCACAGAAAAAAAUGCAGAUGGUUUCAAACAUCUCCUUUUUCGCCAUGUUUGUUAUGUACUUCUUGACUGCCAUUUUUGGCUACUUGACAUUCUAUGACAACGUGCAGUCCGACCUCCUUCACAAAUAUCAGAGUAAAGAUGACAUUCUCAUCCUGACAGUGCGGCUGGCUGUCAUUGUUGCUGUGAUCCUCACAGUGCCGGUGUUAUUUUUCACGGUUCGUUCAUCUUUAUUUGAACUGGCUAAGAAAACAAAGUUUAAUUUAUGUCGUCAUACCGUGGUUACCUGCAUACUCUUGGUUGUUAUCAACUUGUUGGUGAUCUUCAUACCCUCCAUGAAGGAUAUUUUUGGAGUCGUAGGAGUUACAUCUGCUAACAUGCUUAUUUUCAUUCUUCCUUCAUCUCUUUAUUUAAAAAUCACAGACCAGGAUGGAGAUAAAGGAACUCAAAGAAUUUGGGCUGCCCUUUUCUUGGGCCUGGGGGUGUUGUUCUCCUUGGUCAGCAUUCCCUUGGUCAUCUAUGACUGGGCCUGCUCAUCGAGUAGUGACGAAGGCCACUGAAACCCGCCGAGAAAAAGAAACAUCCCUGUUGUCUGCUCAGUCAAGUCCCCACACAUCAGCAAUCUCUCACCACUUCUUUUGCAAGUUUACAGAAGCAAACAGAAAUGUACAGGAUACUUAAAAUGGAAUAACUUUUUGGUUGCAAAACAGAGACAUGGUUCUAUAAUGCUUCAUGUCCCUCCAAGAUUUGAGAUCAAUUUAGGGAUUGUGAAAUUUUUUUUUCAAAUUUCAUACAAUCAUAUUUCCCAGUACUUUUCACAAUCAUUUUUUACCCAUCUAACUCUAUGUUUUGUGGCUUCCCGGUCUCUUAGAACUUUGAAAACAUGAUAUACAAUAAUGUUUAUUUAUUAUACAUCCAGAUUCUGAAAUAAUUUUCCUACUGAUGUUCAGCUCACACUAUCUGUACCUUUUUAGAAGAGAAAAGAAUCUUGAAUUGUAUAUAUUUAUUUUGCUUUACAGAAAAAAAUGGUUUCGUAAAUAAUUUGCCUAUUUUGGUUAACAUAGCACAUGGAGAUAAUCAUCUGAAAGUUAUAGGGCACUGCCACUGCUGAAUCAGAGCAUGCCCAAUAUUUGAGGUGGCUCUGAUUUCCUGGCAGCUGAACUCGGGUAGUCCAGUGGCCUAGCUGGUACCACAUCUAUUCCCAUCCAGAGACAUUCUCUGGCAAGUGUUCUCAGCUGAAAAGUGGUUGGGGAUGAUUCUUACCUUGGUAAUUAAAUGAAGCUACACAUUUGGGUAAUCUAGCAAAUGAAGUAUUUUUUCCCUCUUGGCAACUUGUGUCAGAGUUACUCUGGUCUGAGUCAACUUUCGCUGGGGAAAACCUAUGGAACCUACUGCAAAAAGAUUGUCCAAAAUGCCUAAGAAAAUACUCCUCUGAUGCAUUUAGCCUUCAACCCUACCUGUCUUGCUGAAGGGAGAAAAAUGUUUUAGUACAUUAUAGGCCCAGCAGCUUUUAUUCAUGUCCACCAGCUAGUUGCACAGAGAAUCAUGUGUACCUAACUAAGGAUGAUCUAGGAUAAGUAACUCCUGUUUUAUAUUGAGUAUUUUAGGGAAGUCUUUAAAAGACUUGUUUUAUAUCUAUAAAUCUAGGUUAUUACAAAUACAAGAAUUUUGUACCUUAAAUAAGCCUCAUUUCUAUUUCUUCUUCAUUAAUUCUCCAUCUAGUCUUGUGAAAAAAAAAAAAAAAAAACCCUCAGAGAUAGUCUUUGUGAAGAGCUUCUGACAGAAUCACUGAGUACCUUCCUUCCCCCAGAUGAGGAAGACAAGGGGGUCUCAGUGUCUGUGCUGUCUCCUCUUCUCUUCCCCAACCAAGGACUGUGCCAUUACUGCCCGUCUCAACUGUCCAUGCAGGAGGACAGAGUUGCCUGGUACUCUUACCCUUGUCCCUCUCCUAAAGGGAGCACAAGGAAACUGAAGAGACUGAAAAAGAAGAGAGUUUGUAGCUGAAAAAGAAUAGGGAUAGCAAGGAAACCCAGAACUGCAUUCCCCUAAGUGGGGCCAUCCCAUGUGAUUGAAUUGUCCAUAGCUUGCCUAUGGUGAGAAAUGUGCAUGCUCCGUGAGCUGGUCUCUUGAAACAGGACUUAUGCUUCCUCUAUAUUCUGGUUAAAUUUUCCAAACACAUAAGUUCACUGAGCACAGAUUUCUUAUCCAGAGACAAGUAGAAUCUAACCGCAGACUGUUGGCAGAGUUUCCAGGCACUUAGCCAUGUUCCCUUCCUGACUCAAAUCCCCAAAGGCCUUCACUCUCACUGAGAAUCACACUACUGUCCCAUAGAUAAGGCAGGCAUUGAAGCACCUGUCGUGAUCCUCUAGGGGGGAGAAUGAAAGGUUAUUUCCUGCAUUGCAUCAUCAUAGCUUUUAAUAUAAUGCUACAGAAUCAUAUCCACAUUAGGUUAGAGUUCAGAUAUUUGGAUAUGAAUACCUAACCUAGCCAUAUCCAUGGCCAUCUCUGUUCUUUUCAGCAAUGUUUUCCAUAUUAUAUUAGCAAUGACAGAAACAGAACAAGCCAAGAUCCAGUCAGUUCUUGGGAGCUUGUCUAGAGCACCAAGUAAUGAAAUAGCCAGGUAGUGGGAUGACUGUACCUUUAAAAAUACAUAAUUUAGUUUGCAAGCUAUAUUAUGCUACUUUCUAUUUUCCUUGUUACUUUAUAGCAAUUCAUUUUACCCUCACAAAGUCAAUUUAGAACCUUAUCAUUAACUGGGAUGUGUAGUGAUAUUUUUGGGCCUCUGGGUUUCAUGUGUCAAUACAAGGAAUAUUUAUUUAAAAUAGAUUUAUUUAGAGGAGGCACAGUGUUGUUGAUCUGUGUGACACCACCCAUAUUUUUAAAAACCUUUGUAUGUUUCUCUAAAUUUGUUGUUGACUGAAUAUAAUAGACCCUACCAUAAUUCGUCAAAUAUCACUGAUUAGUUACAUCCUUUGUGUGAGAUUAGCUGUAAAGUAUACUGCUCUUAUUCUUAUUCAGAAUAGUUAAUUGGUAGCCAAAAAUACAUGUAUCACAGAUGUUAGGUCGAAUUUAAACAGCACAGUCAAGUGCUAUGGAAGUUUUUCUGCUAAAUUAGUAGAUUAAAGAAUACUAUACCCUAGGCAUGGGGAGCAGCACGUUUUCCUUUGGUAGGUAGGAUCUCUAUACUAGUGAACAGUGCCAGUUCCACACUUUGGACUUAGAACUGUUCUCUAGUUAUUGUAACACAGAAUACUGUCAAUCCCUAAUUUACUUAAUGUUACUUAUUGGAAGUGGGGCUGAUGAAAUACGCACAGGAGGGAAAUCUACUGUGUUUAGGCACAGGCAGCCCCAGUGUAUAAGGAGAUCAUAUUCCAAAAGGUUGUCAGUUGGUUGUUUGCAACCUGGAAUGUAUUUUCCUUUAGAGACCAGGUUAUCCAUGGUGGUUAGGCCCCUAGAGCAGCUGGAAAAGAUGAUCAAACCAAUAGGUUAGCUGACAUCGAAUAAUGUAAUAGGUUUGCUAAAGAAUCUAACCAUCAAAUAUAAUAUUGUUUCCAGGGAGGGUGUUUGUUCAGAGUUGCCUGUUAGUAGAAUCUGGACUGUCCAUCCCAGCCACAUCCCACCUACUGGACAGUAGGGGUAGAGAUGCCACCAGACUACAGGUGACCAGAUUGGCCUGAAACAUGGUGUCCAGUAAAAACGGGGAGGAAUAAGUCCAUGACUGCUGGAGAGCUUGGUGGUAGGAGGAGGGUGAAGGAGGGUGAGGGGGCCUCUCAUGGGUCAGAAACCUCCAGGGACAUCCCUCAGCUGGUAACUCUGCUGUUGUCCGGAGGGUUCAGGCUUGGUGUGCCUUCUUCUGUUUGUCUGACUUUUGGCUCCUAUGGUUCAUCUCCUGCCCUGCCCACCACAGAAAAGGAUGCUGCUGCAUAGCUUCUCCAAUGUACCAGUCAUUGAGGCCAGCGCGCAGCACUUUUAAUGUUUUUAGUGCUAGUAACUGUGUUUUAACUCUCCAGGAAUAAGCUGGGAGGUUAGAAAACAAGAAAAAAGGGGGAAAAAAAAACCUCUCCACCCACUUUCCUUUUUUACAGUUACAGACCCUGUUGAGAAAAAGAAGCACCCAGAUGGGUGAUGGUGAUAGGGCUUGUGGUGGACACAGGGUUGUGGUAAGAUUCCUCAGUGCUUCGGCGAGCACCUAAGACUAUUACCCUGGAACUGACUGCUUUCUAGAGCUUGAUUCAUGCCUCUAAGCCAGUGGUUCUCAAAGUGUGGCCCCUAGACCAGUAGCAUCAGCAUCAUCGGGGACCUCAUUAGAAUGCAGAUUCUCAGCCCCCUCCCAGACAUGGUGAAGUCAGAAGCUCUCAGGGAGGGACUCAGCAAAUGAUUCUAAAGCGCAUCAAGUUUGAGAACCACCCUAAGCCAAUGAGUCUCCCUUUUACUUCCCAUUAGUCCUCCCUCACCAGAUGAUUCCUAGGACUCAUGGUGCAACAUACAGGAGCCAGGCUUUAGGGAGGGGAGGAAAGGAGCCUGGCGGCAGGGGUCUCUGCAAUGGCAAGAAAGUGAGUGAAUCCAGCGCUGCCACCUGGUUAUCCCCUUCUCGUUGAAAAUAGCAGCGCAGGUGCAAAUUCCUAAACACAGGCUGCCUGCACUCGGUGUUACCUCGGGCUGAGGCAUGAUAAUAUUUUAUUUUUUAAAGCUGUGAGGAAAUGAAAGUGAGGCUUUGGUUGGGGCGAGGCAGUUGUGAAAGAAAUUAAAAUAAAAGACCCUUUGUAAAUGCAGACUUAGAAGAAAUACUGAAUUUGUGUCAGAAGUUCUCCAGUGUUUGUGUUAAUCGUGUGGUGAUAAUCCUGUCCUCCUUUUAAAGCGAAUUCUCUACUGAAAGGUCUGCUCUGCUUAAGGAGCUACAAACUGCUCUCAAAAGAAUGAAAUACUGAGUUCCAAUUCAGUGAGGCACAGUGUUGGACUAUGGCACAUUUAGUUGGAGUCGGGGGGAGGUCAGGAAUAUGAUCAGAUAAUGGAUUUUAUACCUUAGAGCAAAAUCUAUUAGUCUCUCUCAGUUUAUCAAUUUAAAUGGCUUUAGGCUUAUAGGGGGUGUAAACUUUAAGAAUAUAAUUCUCCCAUUCAAGUUUACAGCAAACAUCUAGCCACCUUCAAAACAAAGAAUAUACAGACCAUCAUUUAGCAAUACUAAUACAUGAUUUUCCUUGGGGAUGGCAGGUUUGAGAAUCCUUUAGCAACAGGACAUACUUCCCCUAAAUUACAGUGAAUUAUUUAUAACGAGAUAAAGCUUUCAGGUACAAGCUGAAGGUGGGGUGUCUAACAACUAAAAACUAUCACUAAAUCUCAAAGAGAAAGUUCUUGCAAAAUAUGUAAAGUUCACAAGGUGCAGACAUUUUCCUUCUUUAGGCUUUUAUCUAAGGAAGGGCUAUGAAACUGGGCCCAUCUGUAUACAGGCUCAAAUUUACGUUUUUAAAGGAAGAAUCUAUGCAGCUGAGGCUUAUUGCAGGAAAUACUUCAUUUGUAUGUAAAUAUUAUUGUAAAUAAAUAGGAGGCUGUAUAUUUUUGAAGUUGUUGAUCUGCACUGAAAUAGAAGUCUCUAGGAUCUGCAUAUAAACAAUAAAUGUUUCCUAGAAAUUAGUGGUUUUGUUUGGGAAUUAGAAAAAUUUACAUUCUCUCCCAGGUAACAUAGUUCUCUCAAUGUAAACUUGGAACCUGAAACCCUACUUAAUUUAGAGAAAGAAAUGUCUGAGAAAUAGUUCCCUUGAUUUCUUAUGCUGGCAUUAAGAUCAAUUAUUUAACAGAUAGUCCUCUGAGAUACAAGUAAGGAAUAUUUAGACACAAAUCCUUGUCCUAUAGAAACAGAUAUACCCAAAUGACAAAUUGUUUCUUCAUAAUGAUCUUCCAUUUUUAACACUGAUACCACUACACAGUACAUAUGAAAACAGAAGCUGGGGAGAAGAAUGUUUUUUUCACAAUUGAAUUGCUGCAUUUCUCAAACUUUGGGAUCUAUGAAAGCGGGGAGAGGGAACCUGAAUAUUAAUUAUGAGCACAAAUUUGAAGGAAAGAAAACAAAGAACCAUUAUCUAAUCAAGCUUUGAAAGUCCUGCAUGUUUGCCUUUUAUUUUAGUGUUGACGCCAACAUAGACUGUCUAAGGUAUUUUUUUCCCCAAACACUUGAAUCUUGGUCGUUGGUAUGUAAUCCACUCUCUAGAGUCCAGUGUACUUUAGACUUCAUCUGAGUCCAAUACAUGUACCACACUACUGUUUUAUUAAUGUAAAAACCUUGUAAAUGAAUUUCAGAUGGGUGAUUUAAGUGAGUCACAAGUCACAAAACUUUGCUAUUCAUAGUUAAUCAAAUAGAACUGGGUUUUUUUUUUCAGAGUGUGGUGUAAAUAAAGAAAUAUAAGAAGUUCUGUUCUAUAACUGCUCUGUUAACAUAGUUUUUAAACAUUAAAAAAUGUGAACUAAAAGUA